AGUCACCGAUGCUGGAAGGGUUUCUUUGGCCCUGAGUGAAGAGAGACCCAGAGGGAACACUGAGGUGCCUGCCCAACCACUCUGUCCCGGUUUCCUUCAGCAGGACCAGGUGAGAGAAGCCAUGCUGGUCGUUCAGAUGCCUUUCUCCUUUCCCAUGGCCCACUUCAUCCUCUUUGUCUUUACGGUUUCCACUAUAUUUCACGUUCAGCAGCGGCUAGCGAAGAUUCAAGCCAUGUGGGAGUUACCGGUGCAGAUACCAGUGCUAGCCUCAACAUCAAAGGCACUGGGACCCAGCCAGCUCAGGGGGAUGUGGACGAUCAAUGCAAUAGGCCGCCUGGGGAACCAGAUGGGCGAGUACGCCACACUGUACGCCCUGGCCAAGAUGAACGGGCGGCCCGCCUUCAUCCCGGCCCAGAUGCACAGCACCCUGGCCCCCAUCUUCAGAAUCACCCUGCCGGUGCUGCACAGCGCCACGGCCAGCAGGAUCCCCUGGCAGAACUACCACCUGAACGACUGGAUGGAGGAGGAAUACCGCCACAUCCCGGGGGAGUACGUCCGCUUCACCGGCUACCCCUGCUCCUGGACCUUCUACCACCACCUCCGCCAGGAGAUCCUCCAGGAGUUCACCCUGCACGACCACGUGCGGGAGGAGGCCCAGAAGUUCCUGCGGGGCCUGCAGGUGAACGGGAGCCGGCCGGGCACCUUUGUAGGGGUCCAUGUUCGCCGAGGGGACUAUGUCCAUGUCAUGCCAAAAGUGUGGAAGGGGGUGGUGGCCGACCGGCGAUACCUACAGCAGGCCCUGGACUGGUUCCGAGCUCGCUACAGCUCCCUCAUCUUCGUGGUCACCAGUAAUGGCAUGGCCUGGUGUCGGGAGAACAUUGACACCUCCCACGGUGAUGUGGUGUUUGCUGGCGAUGGCAUUGAGGGCUCACCUGCCAAAGAUUUUGCUCUACUCACACAGUGUAACCACACCAUCAUGACCAUUGGGACGUUCGGGAUCUGGGCCGCAUACCUCACGGGCGGAGACACCAUCUACCUGGCCAAUUACACCCUCCCCGACUCCCCUUUCCUCAAAAUCUUUAAGCCAGAGGCAGCCUUCCUGCCGGAGUGGACAGGGAUUGCCGCAGACCUGUCCCCCUUACUCAAGCACUAAUGCUGGCCCAUUCUUUGAGACCUUUUCUCCUUCUCUGCCUCCCUCAAGAUGAGUGCCCGGGCAUGAGAAGCACAUGGUUCCAUGAGCAGGACCCAUCUCUCUUCUGUGAAGAUGCGUUGGGCUGCAAGUAACAGAAAUCUCAGUGAACAGUGGCCUGGCGUGGUGGCUCAUGCCUGUAAUGCUCGCACUUUGUGAGGCCAGGGUGGGUGGAUCACUUGAGGUCAGGAGUUCAAGACUAGCCUGGCCAACAUGGUGAAACCCCAUCUCGACUAAAAAUACAAAAAUUAGCCAGGCGUGGUGGUGCACACCUGUAAUCCCAGCUACUCGGGAGGCUGAGGCAAGAGAAUCACUUGAACCCAGGAGGCGGAGGUUGCAGUGAGCCAAGAUGGUGCCGCUGCACUCCAGUCUGGGUGACACAGCAAGACUCCAUCUCAAAAAAAAAAAAAAAAAAAAGAAAAGAAAAAGAAAUGAAUGGGUUCAAAGACCAUAAUCAUGCAUAUCACAUAAGACCAGAAGUGGCCCAGGUCCAGGGUCAGUUAAUUUAGCGGCUCCACAAAGUCAUCAGUCACCUGAGCUCCAUCCAUCUUCACAUGCUGUGCUACCAUUUCUUAGCUGUAUCAUCCCAUGGUCCCAAAAGGGCUGCUACACAUCCAGCCAUCACAUGCAGAUAAUUCCUUUCAAAAACAGCAGAAAGAGGCUCGUUCUUGUCUUGGUCCCUUUUGAAGAAUGAAUGAAACCUUCCUAAGCCUUCCAGCAAUUUCCCCCCAACUCCGAUGGGUAGGAAUUGUCACAUACCCAUGUGACCCGAUAGGAGGCAAAAGAAAUGAGACUUCUGGGAUUAGUUUAGCCUCAGAUUCUGCAGCUGAGAAGUUGAUCAGCCACCUCUGAAGGACAUGCAGCUUGCAGAAAAUUAGGGUGGUGUUACCAAGGUGAAAAGGGGAAAUGGCUUUAGAGUAGACAACAGAGAUGCCCUGAGGGGUUGUGUAGGUUGUUCACUGCAGGAAGUCCCCUGGUUAAGAAGGCAAGUGGGGUUUAAACAGACCCACAGUCUACUCAUCAAACCAGGUGUCCUUGGCAUUGUGUCCACCCAGAGAGCUCACUGUUUUCUUUUCUUUUUCUUUUCUUUUUUUUUUUUUUUUUGAGAUGGAGUCUUGCUGCAUCCCCCAGGCUGGAGUGCAGUGGCAUGAUCUUGGCUCACUGCAGCCUCCGCCUCCCAGGUUCAAGCGAUUCUCCUGCCUCAGCCUCCCGAGUAGCUAGGAUUACAGGUGCGUGCCACCACGCCCAGCUAAUUUUUAUAUGUUUAGUGGAAAUGGAGUUUCACCAUGUUGGUCAGGCUGGUCUCAAACUCCUGACCUCAUGAUCCGCCUUCCUCGGCCUCCCAAAGUGCUGGGAUUACAGGUGUUAGCCACUGCGCCCGGCCCUAGAGCUCACUGUUUUCUAGUUAGUCCAUCUGGAAGUGGAGCCUUUUUCCAGUUUGCACAAAUGUGCCAUAUUGGCUUGUAGCUGGCAUGCAUCCAAGUCCAUAGGUCCUGCCUCUUCAAUCCUGGCUUUCUAGGGCCUGGGAUGAUCAUUGCUAGAACUGAGAGACCAGCCUGGCUCAGUGAACUUCAGGGCGUUCCGUUCAUUCUUUCAGUAAAUGUUUGCAGCACAUGUGUUACAUGUCAGGCAGUGAAACCCCCCACAGCAGCCUUCCCUCUCAGAGGAUACAUUUGUAACCAUUACACAGUCAUCAAAGGAAUAAUUUUUUUUAAUCACCAGUGUGCAUACAGUCAUGGAGUUGGGUAUUCCCAGCUACCAGGGAGGCUGAGGUGGGAGGAUUGCUUGAUGCCAGGAGUUAGGGAAUAUAGUGCACCGUGAUUGGACUUGCGAAUAGCCACUGCACUGCGGCCUGGACGACGUAGUGAUACCCUGACUCUUAUAAAUAAAUAAAUGAAUAAACACAAUUAUGACUUUGCGGAUGGGA